GCAAAGAGAGAGAGAGAGAGAGAGAGAGAGAGAGAGAGGGAUAGUAUAUGAAGGGCUAUAGGCAGCCCCAGAAGAGCAAGAAAGGCAAAGACCAAGCAGGCAUCAGAGCUGGAUCCUGACAUAGCAAGCAAUUCAGACACCUGCCGGGCAUCGGGGCAGGGUGAAGUCUUCUUACCAGAAGAGAAAUCUGGAGCAGGGAAGUUGGGGGACCUGUGUGGGGUAGGGAGUAGGUUUGUAAAUUGGAAUGUUGUGGUAGAGUAAGACUGGAAAGGUUAGGUCAUUCAUUAUGGAGAUAGUCUGAAAUAAAGACAUCAGGGAUCAUGGAGUGUAGUUAGGAUAUAAGCAUUUUGUACAAGAGUUUGAUGCUUGUUUCCUUUAUAUUUUUACCCUGUGGAGCCCUUGGGAGUUCAAGUAUGUGUCUAUUGAGAGAGAUCCAUCAUAGCACCUUUAUUUAUUUAUUAUUACUAUUUAUUAGAAAAUGAGCAAUGCUUAACCUCUCUAGAUAGCUUUAAUACAGUGACAUGACUUCAUGUUGUGGAGUUGGACAGGUUAUAUGAACAUGCAGAAAUGUAGCUAUUCAGUUUCUCAGUUUUGGUGAUGACCCAUGUCAAAUAAUUUUUAAAUUGUCUAAUAUGAGAUUAGGCUCUUACACUGAGAAAUUAAAGUAAAACAAGCUAUUUAUUAACAGAGUAGGUGGACUAAUCCUUUGCUAGAGUAAAUAUGAGGAGCUACAUCAACACACAUAUACAUUCUCUACGUAAGGUUAAGAUGUAUGUAGCUAAAUAUAUUCAUUAGUAUUACUUAGGAGAUGCUCUUUCUUUUGUCAUGUUUCUUUGGCAAAAGCUAGCAGUUCUGUUAGCAGUGGUUUUGAUGAUAAAAUCCUGUAAUUCAAGAGGUUGGCUUAUUCAACUAAACAACUGCUACCUUGGGCAAUACUGGACCAACUGCGAGGGGACUGUUUUCUUGAGACCUGGAAAGCUGUUCUGUUUGCUAAACAAAGGAAUUGUUGAUUUCAGUGAUUUAAUUCCCCUUUUGGCUAAAGGCUGCUGAAUGAAAACAGUGCUUGUUUGGGAAGGAAUCUGUUGCUAAGGCAACUGAUAUCUCCUUAAUUAUUGGCCAAUAUUCCCAAAUGAGAUUGGUCUCUUUUGACUGUUGGAAAUAACCAAAUUAUCCUGAGCACUUUCAAGUCUUGAAUUUUGUGGUAAUGGCGGGGGUUGGGGGAGGGAUUUCUCUCAAGUAUAUAAACAGAUAUCUCCCAUUUGGGUUGGCAUAGUGUGAGCACUGUGUUUAUGAGGGUAAAAAUAUAGAUGAUAUUUGCAAAACCUCUUUUAUUGUAAGAGAUCUUAUUACUUAAGACGAGUUGCAAUUCUGAGAUGAGUGACCUAUGUUUAAUCUUUUUUUAAAAAAUGAAUUAUUUGAUUUCUGUAAGAAAAUAGAAUACAUCUAAUCAUUUAUCCUCAAGAAUAGGCAGAUAUAUGGAGAAACUUGUAAGUAUUAUUUGAAUGAUGCUAACAAGGACUGUCUUCAGAAGCGUCUGCAGCCAUUUAUGUGAGGUUCUUUACUUGAAUGUUUCUAGCACUGCAUAUGCUGACCUUGGAGAGUGACCUCUUUUCUGUCUAUUACUUUGUAGGAUCAUGUAAAAGACCUGUGGUUUCUUGUCUCUUGGCAGUACAGUUGUUUGAUCAUUUAAAAUUAAUUGAAGCUUUGAAUAUAGUCAGGCUCAAGUUCUAGUGUAUUCAUAUCAUACUUUGUAAUUGCUCUCUAGUGUGAAGGACAUACUAAAACAUCAGUACAGUUCUUACAAAAUGGGAAUUUGUCUUUAUAAUUUUAUUGUAUGUCUUUUAAAUUCUUAUAGUGAAUCAUAGAGAUCACACAUUAUUAUCUUAUAUCCUUACAACAAAACGGGAAUUCACUGUUCUUUGGUACUUGUCCUGUGACAAGCCUGGUGAGUAUUGAUGAAAUUCUUCUAAUAUUACUUGGGGUAUCCCAGAUCUUCCAGUUGAGUGAACAUGAGGUUCUGAAGUGUGACUGUUUAUGAUUUCUGUGUUGUAGAACCAUGAAAAUUUUGUAGGAGUCUCACAUGAAAGGCUUUUGGCACAAUAGCACUGAGUAAAAUCUGUUUUGUGAUACUUCUGAAUGGUUAUAGUUCUUACUUAGGAGUAGUCUUUCCAUGUUUCAUUCAUAGAGAUGACAUUGGGUUUAUACCUUGGGUUGAAUUGAAUAUAAAAAGCUUUGUGUACUAUGUAUUGGAAGAAUACUUGAGUUGGAUUUCAUGUACAUAUUUAUUAUCUAUCCUAGAUUUAUGAAAUUUCACUCUUCAUUUUAAAUAGCUUCAAGAAGUAAAUACAAGAUUCACUUGAUGAAAAUAUUAAAAUACAUGAAAAGGACAAUAUCCUGCGAAACUGUUGACUAAAAUAUAAGCACAGAACCACAGAAUAUAAGUUCAAAGCUGUCCCUACAUGUCUCUAGAGUAUCAUUAAUCUAGUUCUCACUAGGGUUUUAGAGUAUCUAAGUAGGUUUUACACUAUCUACUGAAGUUCUUCCAUAUCAGACUAUAAAUAUAAGCAUACAGUUAAAUCUGUGAUACAUUUUGAAUUAGCCUCCCUUUUUAGGACUCUUUUGAGCUUGUCUUAUUUAAAAUAUGUUGAAGUAUGAACUAUCAGACUUCAAAAACAUUGUUCUUUGAAAAACAUUUUUGUGCUGUAUUUUUAAAUUCCUUGAUAUUUAUAAUUAUUUAAAAGAUUUUUGUUGUAGUCAUCUAGUUUAUAAGAUUAAUUUUUUCCUGGAUUAUUGUAGGAAAAAAACAAGUUUUUAAAUAAGAUAAUGUAAAGAGAAUUUAUAUAUUUAUGUUGAUUAGAUCAUAAAAAUUUGACCCAAGUUAUUAUAUAUGUUAAAUUCUAUGAAUUUAUUACUUUGUUUUGUCACAUAUUAGUUGACUCAAUUUUCCAACAUUUCCAGCAUUUUGCCCUUUUCUCAGAUACUUUUUUUUUUUUUUUUCUGGAGUCUUGCUCUGUUGCCCAGGCUGGAGUGCAGUGGCACAAUCUCAGCUCACUGUAACCUUUGCCUCCUGGAUUCAAACGAUUCUCCUGCCUCAGCCUCCUGAGUAGCUGGGAUUAUAGGCACGCACCAUCACACCCAGCUAAUUUUUGUAUUUUUAGUAGAGAUGGGGUUUCACCAUGUUGACCAGACUGGUCUUGAACUCCUGACCUCAAAUGAUCCUCCCACUUUGGCCUCCCAAAUUGCUGUGAUUACAGGCAUGAGUCAUCAUGCCCAGCCUCAGAUUAGUUGAAGAUCAAAGAUAUAGAGAGAAUAUUUUGUUAGCAAUUUCUUAGCUUUUUUUUUAACCUUAUAUAUUUUGGUUUUUUUUUUUCCUGGAGACUUGUACUUAGUACUAACUUCAGUUUGCAUAAUAUAUAUUUAUAUAUUCAAUGUGAAUAUUUUAUAUACAUACCUAUGACAAAUCUUAAUUUUUAUAUACAAAUAUAUGGCAGUGUUCUUUUUCUUUCUGCAAUGGUAGGUUUUUUCUUCAAUUCAAGACUAAUUCAGUAUUUUAUUUACCUUUAUUUAUAACCACGUGUGGUAUCUUUCUUUUGAGAAAGCAUUGACACUCUAUUGCUAUUAAACACUUUCACUGGGUGAGAUAGAACUGUUGUUGACUGUACAUUAUGUGUGUGCCAGAGAAUAUAAAGGAACAAUGGAGAAAUGUCCCAUCACAAUUUUGAAAGGGUCUAUUUUAAAUGCUACGUGUUUCUACUAGAAUAUAGAGCUGUAAUUUGGAACAGGAGUGAAGAAAGAGACUUGUAGAAUUUAAGUUGCCUAUCUCCUAUCUCCUAACUCAUUGGGAGGCUGGGUCUUCAUUGUGAAGUCUCUCAUGUAUACCUGUUAAAUGAAUUUGUAUGCCUUUUGUCCUAUUAAAAAAUUAAUUAAUAAAGGGCUCGGACAAAUUGAAACACUGGGUCUACUCAGGAAAUAUUUUUAUAGGUGCAGUUCGAAUGUUUGAAUUAGGAUGUAACAUUAGAAAACGUAAAGGAGCUGGGCAUGGUGGCUCGUGCUUGUAGUCCCAGCAGGAGGCUGAGGCAGGAGUUUCGCUUGAGCCCAGGAGUUGGAGUUGAAGGUUGCAGUGAGCUAUAAUUACAUCACUGCAUUCCAACCUGGGCAAUAGAGUAGCGGGGUGGGUUGGAGGCGAAACAAGAAUAAAAUGAUACAACAAAAACAAAAAAGCAAAACAACAAAAAGAGAAAAUGUAAAGGCUAUGUAAGGCUUGCCUCAGGCAAAAAUUAUCAAAUAGGCCAGGCGCAGUGCCUCACACAUGUAAUGUCAGCCUGGCCAACAUGGUGAAACUUGUCUCUACAAAAAAUACAAAAUAUUAGCUGGAUAUGGUGGCAGGUACCUGUAAUCCCAACUACUCAGGAGGCUGAGGCAGGAGAAUUGCUUGAACCCAGGAGGCAGAGGUUGCGGUGAGCCAAGAUCGCACCACUACACUCCAGCCUGGACAACAGAGUUGAAACUCUGUCUUUAAAAAAAAAAAAUUACCGAAUAAAUAUACAUUUAUCUUUGGUGUUUCCCAACUUAGAUUUGAAUUGUUGUAUCUCUCCCCUAAACCCUGCCCUGUGCUCUUGUGUGCCCUGUGACUGAUUAGUAUCCUUGUCUCUGUCACUCCAGGUCUGCUCUCUUUUUCUUUUCCCUUUCUGCACUUCAAGCCUUCCUUACCUCCCAUGCCCUUGUACCCUUUUAACUUUCUUUAAAAAUGGCCAGUGCUUUAUUUCAGUUUCACUGUGUCCAUUCUCUAGAAAUUAAUCUGAUGCACUAAUCACCAUUAAAUUGAUAAUGCUUGAUAAUGUCUUGCCUUGAUCUGGUUUGCCAUCUUAAUUAGAAUUUUAACUUAGCUUUUUAGAGGAGAACAUUUCAAGACAUACCACCUUGAUUGUUGAACUUGGGUUAGGUAAUAUUUCAAGGUGGUUCAUAAAGGUAUUUAUUUUAAAGGAAAAAGAACACUGAGAGCCCAGCAUGCAUAUCCACCUUCAAGAUUUAAUAAUUUGAGAUUUCAACUGUCCCUUAAGGAAAGCUGAUUUUAGAAGAGAGAAGGUAAAACUAUUCAAUAAUUAUUAUCCAUAAUAAAAUAUAUUAUAGUUCCUUUUUCUUAGCCAAUUAAAGGAAAAUACUAUGUAUUAAUAGGAUAUGUAAUUUGGGGGUAUAGAAAACAUUUUUUUAACUCAUCUAAUUAUUUUUAGUUUUUGUGAUGAUGACUACUGAUUUGUCCUGUGCUACAUAUAAUUCUUUGUCACAGUUUUAUUAGCAUAUAUUAUAGCCAAGUGCUUGCUUGGCUAUGAAGAGGGCAUUUUUAUUCUGUUCCAUGUUAUUUUUCUUACCAAAAAAUGCAACAAAAAACUAAAGUCUAUUCAAAAAAAGCUUAUUUCAUUAUUUAAAAAAAUUCUUUCCCAUAUUCCAUAUUUCUUUUGUUAGUGUAAUAACCAAUUUUUUUUUCCAGAAAUUUAACCUCUCCCCUGCUUGUGUCAUUCAGGUUUGGCCCAAAAGCAAACAAUGGAAGUACUUCUGACCUACCUUUGUUAGAAACUUUGCAUAUCUAAAUCAUUGCUUGCAAGAGUGUGAGGGAAAGUAAGAGUAAAGAGGAUAGAAUAUAAGAGAUUGCUCUGUCCUAAGAUAUUGAUGGUCUAUUGGGAAAUCAGAUAACCACAUAUGACACACUCUAUCAGCAAGCCAGAUUACUUUUAAGUUCUAAGAUAUGUGAAAAAGUUAAUAGUAUCAGUCUUCAGAGAGAAAAGAGAAAUUACAGCAGGCUUGAGAUGUCAUAGAAGUUUUAGACUAAACUUUGGUGAUAAAAGGGAAGAGGACCUUUGAGAUGAAAAUUUUCAAAUAUUCCUAUCAGAAUUCUCAGCCCAGAGAUGAUACAUGCAGCAAACUGAGAAAAAGAGGAAAAAAGAAUCGCUUCUAGGCUUCUUCAUUUGUCCACGUGAAGUCUGUCCAAACCCAGUGUGACAGAGUUGUAGUUUCAAGCACGCUGUUCUUAGAUCUUAGACUGCUGUGACAAAAUACCUUAGACUGGUUGGCUUAAACAACAGAAAUCUAUUUCUCACACUUCUGGAGGCUAGGAAAUCUAAGAUCAAGGUGCCUCCAGAUUCUGUUCUUGCUGAGUUCGUCUCCUGGCUUGUCCUAGAAGGGCUGUCUUAUCCUUAUGUUCUUACAUGGCUUUUCCUUGAUGAAUUUACUUGUGGAGAGAGGUAGAGAAAGAGGAAAAGAGAGAGGGGAAGAGCGGGUGGGGAGAGAGAGAGAGAGAGAGAGAGAAAACGAAACGGGAAGGGGGAGAGAGAGUUGUCUCUUUUUGUAAGGGCCCAGAUGCUGUUAUGAAGGCCCCAUCUUCAUGACCUCAUCUAAGCCUUAUUACUUCCCAAAGGCCCUAUCUUCAAAUACCAUCACAUUAGGGAUUAGGGUUUCAACAUAUUAAUUUUGAGGGACACAAACAUUCAGACCAUAACACAACCCAGAACUCAUCUGUGUUAUGGUGAGUCCCACCCUUGCCUUAAUUCCCUAUCUUCCCCCAGAAUCCUAGAAGAUAAGACACACUGCUCAAAUGACUUAGGACUUAGUUUAGGGCACUCCCUUUAGGGUCAUAUGUUGUAUUAGUUCAGAUUUCAAGUAUUUAUAGAUAUUUUUGAAUUUAUGUUUAAUUCUUUAUUCAAAAUGAGCUUUUUGAGAGCUCAUAAUUGGCUUACCUUAUGAUUCCAUAAAAGUGAAUAUUUGGCUUUAGACAAGUGUAAUUUGUUUAUUUAACAACCAUUUAAUGGAUGCCUAUGAUGUGCUUCUUUCUGAUUUUUGGCCUAGGGGUUUGUUCAAUUUCCUAUGCCUCUUACAAGGGCAGAAUUGAGGUGGGGCCUUUUAGUUUUUCUGCGUCCUUGCCAGCCUUUGGUGUUGCUGUUAUUUUUAUUUUAGCCAUUUUAAUAGAUGUAUGGUGAUAUCUCAUUAUGGCUUUAAUUUGCAUUUCCUUAAUGGCUGAUGUUGUCAAAGAUCUCUUAAUGUGCUUAUUUUCCAUCUGUAUAUCCUUUUUUGUGAAAUACCUGUUCAGUGUCUUGCCCAUUGUGUUAGUCUGGUUUUUUGUUGCUAUGAAGGAAUAUCUGAAGCUGGGUAAUUUGUAAAGAAAAGAGGUUUAUUUGGCUCAUGGUUCUACAGCUUGUACAAGAAGCAUGGCACCAGCAUCUGCUUCUGGUGAUGGCCUCCAGCUGCUUCCACUCAUGGCAGAAGGCAAAGGGGAGCCAGUGUGCACAGAGGUCAUGUGGUGAGGGGUGGGAGGAGAGAUGCCAGGCUCUUUUUCACAACUAGCUCUCACUGAAUCUAAUAGACCAAGAACUCACUUAUUACUGCAAGGAUGAUACCAAGCCAUUUGUGAAUGAUCCCAUCCCUGUGAACCAAACACCUCACGUUAGGCCCCACCUCCAACACUGGGGAUCAGAUUUCAACAUGAGAUUUGGAGGGGUCAAACAAACCAUAUUGAAACUAGAGCACCCACUUUCUAAUUGUUUUUUUUUAAUAAUUGAGUUUUGAGAAUUUGUAAAUAUAUUCUACAUGCUACUCUUUGUUGGAUAUGCAGUAGUUUGCAAAUGUUUUCUCUCAGUCUGCAGCUACUCUUUUCAUCUGCUUAAUAGGGUCUUUUGCUGAGCAAAGGCUUUUAGUUUUGAUGAAGUCCAAUUUAUUUUUCUUUGUGGGUUGUGCUUUUGGCAUCAAUUCUAAGAACUAGUUUUGUAGCUCUAGGUCCUGAAAACUUUUCUUCUGUUUUUAUCUGAAAGUUUUAUAGUCUUAUGUUUUACAUUAAGUCUGUGGUCCAGUUUGAGUUAAUUUUUUGUAUAAGGUGGGAGUUUUUGGUGAAGAUUCACUUUUUUGCUGAUGUCCAGUUGCUCUAUUCUUUAUCAUAAAGGUCUUCAUCCUCAUCAUCUUACCAUUGAAUAGGCUGAGGUGAAGGAGGCGGAAAAGGAGGAGUUUGUCUUGCUGUCAGAGGCGGAAGAAAAUCCAUGUGCAUCUGGCCAUCUGAAGAGGUUUUGGCUUACUACUGCCUCAAGCACAAUAAUAUAUUCAGGGCCCUUGCUGUGUGUGAGCUAGGGGGUGGCAUGACAUGCUUGGCUGGGCUCAUGGUUGCUAUUUCUGCAGAUGUCAAAGAAGUUCUGUUAACUGAUGGGAAUGAAAAGGCCAUCAGAAAUGUGCAAGACAUCAUCACAAGGAAUCAGAAGGCUGGUGUGUUUAAGACCCAGAAAAUAUCAAGCUGCGUUUUACGAUGGGAUAAUGAGACAGAUGUCUCUCAACUGGAAGGACAUUUUGACAUUGUUAUGUGUGCUGACUGCCUGUUUCUGGACCAGUACAGAGCCAGCCUUGUUGAUGCAAUAAAGAGAUUACUCCAGCCCAGGGGGAAAGCGAUGGUAUUUGCCCCACGCCGAGGGAAUACUUUAAACCAGUUUUGCAAUCUAGCUGAAAAAGCUGGUUUCUGUAUCCAAAGACAUGAAAAUUAUGAUGAACACAUUUCAAACUUCCACUCCAAGUUGAAAAAGGAAAACCCGGACAUAUAUGAAGAAAACCUUCAUUACCCGCUUCUGCUUAUUUUGACCAAACAUGGAUAGAAGAUUAAGCUUCUCAAAGACGAAGAAACGUAUCAAGUGCAUAGGGAAUAUUUUUACAAAAACGGAAAUCUGUAAGGGGUAUAAUCGCCUGCCUGCGCCCUUUGCAGCAUUUCACGUGUGGGCUAUGGACUCCACCUGUCCUCACCCACGUUAUUCCCCAGCUGCCCUCUCCAGCUCCCUCCCCGCCUCUUUUUACACUCUGCUUGUUGCUCGUCCUGCCCUAAACCUUUGUUUGUCUUUAAAUGUGUAUAAGCUGCCUGUCUGUGACUUGAAUUUGACUGGUGAACAAACUAAAUAUUUUUCCCUGUAAUUGAGACAGAAUUUCUUUUGAUGAUACCCAUCCCUCCUUCAUUUUUUUUUUUUUUUUGGUCUUUGUUCUGUUUUGGUGGUGGUAGUUUUUAAUCAGUAAACCCAGCAAAUAUCAUGAUUCUUUCCUGGUUAGAAAAAUAAAUAAAGUGUAUCUUUUUAUCUCCCUCCAA